GUCGCGCUGUUCCGGAGGGUGCCUGCGGCGGCUGAAUUCCUGUGCUGCGACUGUGCCGCGCCCAGAGCAGCAGCAACAGCGAAGAUGCGAGGCCAUUACCUGUUUGAUCCCUGUCGGAAACCUGGCACGGGCCAACUUUUCCCGAUUAUCACGCCAAGAAGUUGCAAGGACUAGUCGAAGACUCGGAGGGGCCAGGGCGAGGGCGCGCUCCCCCGCGCGCUGCCUCGUCCCUCCUCCGUCCGGCCGCCCGAGCUCCCGGCCUCUCUCCCGCCCGCGCUCACUCCCUCCGCCCGCCUCCCUCCUCUGGCCCCCAUCAGAAGGGCAACAGGGCGAGGGGGUCCGGCGAAAUUCGGACCGGAGCAGCUGGACAUGCACGGUGUCCGCCGGGCGCAGGGGCCGACCACACGCAGUCGCGCAGUUCAGCAUCCGCGUGCCAGUCUCGCCCGCGAUCCCGGGCCCGGGGCUGUGGCGUCGACUCCGACCCAGGCAGCCAGCAGCCCGCGCGGGAGCCGGACCGCCGCCGGAGGAGCUCGGACGGCAUGCUGAGCCCCCUCCUUGGCUGAAGCCCGAGUGCGGAGAAGCCCGGGCAAACGCAGGCUAAGGAGACCAAAGCGGCGAAGUCGCGAGACAGCGGACAAGCAGCGGAGGAGAAGGAGGAGGAGGCGAACCCAGAGAGGGGCAGCAAAAGAAGCGGUGGUGGUGGGCGUCGUGGCCAUGGCGGCGGCUAUCGCCAGCUCGCUCAUCCGUCAGAAGAGGCAAGCCCGCGAGCGCGAGAAAUCCAACGCCUGCAAGUGUGUCAGCAGCCCCAGCAAAGGCAAGACCAGCUGCGACAAAAACAAGUUAAAUGUCUUUUCCCGGGUCAAACUCUUCGGCUCCAAGAAGAGGCGCAGAAGAAGACCAGAGCCUCAGCUUAAGGGUAUAGUUACCAAGCUAUACAGCCGACAAGGCUACCACUUGCAGCUGCAGGCGGAUGGAACCAUUGAUGGCACCAAAGAUGAGGACAGCACUUACACUCUGUUUAACCUCAUCCCUGUGGGUCUGCGAGUGGUGGCUAUCCAAGGAGUUCAAACCAAGCUGUACUUGGCAAUGAACAGUGAGGGAUACUUGUACACCUCGGAACUUUUCACACCUGAGUGCAAAUUCAAAGAAUCAGUGUUUGAAAAUUAUUAUGUGACAUAUUCAUCAAUGAUAUACCGUCAGCAGCAGUCAGGCCGAGGGUGGUAUCUGGGUCUGAACAAAGAAGGAGAGAUCAUGAAAGGCAACCAUGUGAAGAAGAACAAGCCUGCAGCUCAUUUUCUGCCUAAACCACUGAAAGUGGCCAUGUACAAGGAGCCAUCACUGCACGAUCUCACGGAGUUCUCCCGAUCUGGAAGCGGGACCCCAACCAAGAGCAGAAGUGUCUCUGGCGUGCUGAACGGAGGCAAAUCCAUGAGCCACAAUGAAUCAACGUAGCCAGUGAGGGCAAAAGAAGGGCUCUGUAACAGAACCUUACCUCCAGGUGCUGUUGAAUUCUUCUAGCAGUCCUUCACCCAAAAGUUCAAAUUUGUCAGUGACAUUUACCAAACAAACAGGCAGAGUUCACUAUUCUAUCUGCCAUUAGACCUUCUUAUCAUCCAUACUAAAGCCCCAUUAUUUAGAUUGAGCUUGUGCAUAAGAAUGCCAAGCAUUUUAGUGAACUAAAUCUGAGAGAAGGACUGCCAAAUUUUCUCAUGAUCUCACCUAUACUUUGGGGAUGAUAAUCCAAAAGUAUUUCACAGCACUAAUGCUGAUCAAAAUUUGCUCUCCCACCAAGAAAAUGUAAAAGACCACAAUUGUUCUUCAAAAACAAACAAAACAAAACAAAACAAAAUUAACUGCUUAAAUGUUUUGUCGGGGCAAACAAAAUUAUGUGAAUUGUGUUGUUUUCUUGGCUUGAUGUUUUCUAUCUACGCUUGAUUCACAUGUACUCUUUUCUUUGGCAUAGUGCAACUUUAUGAUUUCUGAAAUUCAAUGGUUCUAUUGACUUUUUGCGUCACUUAAUCCAAAUCAACCAAAUUCAGGGUUGAAUCUGAAUUGGCUUCUCAGGCUCAAGGUAACAGUGUUCUUGUGGUUUGACCAAUUGUUUUUCUUUCUUUUUUUUUUUUUUUAGAUUUGUGGUAUUCUGGUCAAGUUAUUGUGCUGUACUUUGUGCGUAGAAAUUGAGUUGUAUUGUCAACCCCAGUCAGUAAAGAGAACUUCAAAAAAUUAUCCUCAAGUGUAGAUUUCUCUUAAUUCCAUUUGUGUAUCAUGUUAAACUAUUGUUGUGGCUUCUUGUGUAAAGACAGGAACUGUGGAACUGUGAUGUUGUCUUUUGUGUUGUUAAAAUAAGAAAUGUCUUAUCUGUAUAUGUAUGAGUCUUCCUGUCAUUGUAUUUGGCACAUGAAUAUUGUGUACAAGGAAUUGUUAAGACUGGUUUUCCCUCAACAACAUAUAUUAUACUUGCUACUGGAAAAGUGUUUAAGACUUAGCUAGGUUUCCAUUUAGAUCUUCAUAUCUGUUGCAUGGAAGAAAGUUGGGUUCUUGGCAUAGAGUUGCAUGAUAUGUAAGAUUUUGUGCAUUCAUAAUUGUUAAAAAUCUGUGUUCCAAAAGUGGACAUAGCAUGUACAGGCAGUUUUCUGUCCUGUGCACAAAAAGUUUAAAAAAGUUGUUUAAUAUUUGUUGUUGUAUACCCAAAUACGCACCGAAUAAACUCUUUAUAUUCAUUCAAAGAAUAAUCUUCCAACAUGUAUUUAUUGAGCGUCCAUUAUGUGCCAGUAACUGAAGUAGCAACUGGAAGUAAACAUUGUAUAAUGCAGAUAAGGUCACUGUCCUCAGAUAGUCUACAGUCUAGAGAGUCAUAUUAACAUGAACACUUUAAAGUGUGUUUAUUUUACUAGUUACUGUACUUGCACUUCAGAUUGGUACAAAGGAAUUCACAUUCCCGUUCAGUAGUCAAAUUAUACAAAUGAGGCGUUUGUGCUAGUAUUUUCUCUGCCACUCACAGUGUCAUUUCCCCUCUCUGUUGCUUAUUUCUCUCCUCUCUAGAGGGAAUACACAGGACUAAAUAGUGUCCUUUCUACCUUUGAGAACUGAAGGAAAAUGUAAAUUUUUUUAAAUGUUGAUGACUUUUCUCUAGCUCCCCAAAGCUGCAUUGUCUGGCAAUGAACACUUUGAGAACAGUCAAUACAGAUGGUCUCUGACUUACAGUAGUUCAACUUACAUUUUUUCGGGGGCUUUACAGUGGUACAGAAGCAAUAGGCAUUUAGUAGAACUCAUACUUUACCAUACAACCAUUUUGCUUUUUAUUUCCAGUACACUAUUCAAUAAAUGACAUGAGCUAUUCAACACUUUUUAAUUACAAAAUUUGCUUUGUAGUACAUGAUUUUGUCCAACUGUAAGCUAAUAUAAGCGUUCUAAGCACAUUUAAAGUAGGCUAGGCUAAGCUAUGAUGUUUGCUAGGUUAGGUGUAUUAAAUGCAUUUUCAACUUAAGAUGGGUUUAUUGGUAUGUGACCCCCAUCGUAAGUGAAGGAUCAUCUGUAUAUGGAGGGAAGAAUUGUGAAAUACAUAAAACGUAGUUGACUAGUGCUUUUCAGAGCAUCUGCAAAUAAAAUUACUGGGGCCCCAAACAGCCUGCUUUUGCAAGGAGGGGAGACUCCUCAUUUCUAAGAUGUUUGGACCAGAUUCAGCAUGAGCUCCUAUCCCUGCCCACCCCAGCCCAGUCUAAGUCACCUUGUAAUUUCAUGAGAUAAGUCCUCCUCAUCCUGCUUCAUCCUGCCUGAGCUCUAAACACACCUACAUGAGGUACGCUCACCUGCCUAGCUAUCUUGGAUGCAGGAUCCUUUGUACCAUGUUUUAAAAAUCAGGAGAUGCUCACUCAACCACCUCUCCCUAUUAACUCUUACUAAUUUUCAAUCAGUAGGGAAAAGUAGUGCAUUGUCUCCCUCUUUCUCUAAGAACUUUAAAGUUUGGUCACUGACUACUUCAGUUGCUGGUCUUGCUUUUUCUGUUGUUCAGAAAUAGUGUAGGUCUGCUGGUAGUAAGCAAAUUAGCACUAUGUGGGUCUCAGGGAUGCCUGCGUUAAUAGGAUGGAGUCAAAAUGCCCAGGAAGAAUCCUUUACCCCCAGCAUUCUUUUUGAGCUGCCUUAAAGUUGCUUUAAACAGACAGUGGUGUUAAAAUAAAUUAAUAAGUAAAUAAAUAGUCCUCAAACCUUCCUACAAGUGAUGAUAUCAAUACUUUCACACAUCUUCAUUACACACACACAUACACACACACCCUUUCCCACCCCAUCCCCUCAUGCACAUCCUUUAGUAGCAUUCCUCCUGGCAGAAAAUACUAGUCCUGCCACAUAACUGAUGAAAGAAAAAAAGACUCUAGUCAAAUAGUUGUGGGAAACACUUCAAAUACUAUUGGGUCUCAGAUAUUAGCUCACAUCAGAAUCACCUGGAAGGCUUGUAAGACUCAGAUCACUGGACUUCACCUUCAGAGUUUCUGAUUGAGUGAGUCUUGUGUGGGCCCAAAACUUGGCAUUUCUAACAAGUUUCCAGGUGAUGCUGAGGCUGUUGAUCCUCGGGACUUUGAGAACCACUGGUAUUAGUUCAUUCUCACGCUGCUAUAAAGAUACUACCUGAGACUGGGUAAUUUAUAAAGGAAAGAGGUUUAAUUGACUCACAGUUCUGCAUGGCUGGGGAGGCCUCAGGAAACUUACCAUCAUGGCAGAAGAUGAAGGGGAAGCAAGGACCUUUUCCACGUGGCAGCAGGAGAGAGAAUGGGAAAGCGCCACUUAUCAAACAGAUUUAGUGAGAACUUCCUCACUAUAUGAGACAGCAUGGGGAAACCGCCCCGAGGAUCCAAUCACCUCCCACCAGGUCCCUCCCUCAACACAUUGGGAUUACAACUCUAAAUGAGAUUUAGGUGGGGACACAGAGCCAAACCAUAUCACACUGGCAUACACUAUUCCUUUCUUCAGGAUUAGCGUGCAUUAGCAAAUUAAUUUCUGAAAAGUCUUGUGUUAAAGAAAUCUGUUUAACUUUUACAAAUGCUGAGACAAACUUAUUGGGCCACAAAGCCACAUUUUCAUGGAGCGUCUAUUAACAUUGCAGUAGAGUGGUAGUCCUCAAGCUUUUUAUGUGUACCUGAAUCACCUGUGGUGUUUUAUAUGCUUCUUUUGUUUUAAGCUUGGCCUGGGAAUCUCCUGAAUCUGAUACCUACUGUUCUAUGCCACAGCACUUAAUGUCAGUGUUCUAUGGCAUGGCACUUAAUGUCAGUUUUCCACCCCAUCUGUGAACGUGUAUUCAAUCAUUAUACUGUAUUUAGCCUGAGAAUGAAUAUGGAAAAGAAAACAACACUUUCUUCAGGCUUUUUGCAACUUUUUAAAAGCAAAACAGGCUCCAAUUCCCCCUCCCAGGAGUUUUGUUUGUAUCCAAAGAGAGGACAUGCUCAUUGCCAUGGAAUCCUUAAAGGACUGAGAGGGAAGUGAUCUGUGGCACUCCUCCCCUCCCUAACCAGUACAUUUGUUCCAGUUUUAAGCCAGUCAAGCUCACCGAAGAGUUUUUCAAAGACCUUAGCUACAUGGAUUUAACUUUACCAAGCAUCCAUUGUCCAAAUGAACAUAUGAGGGAAAAUGAAUAUCUCUUCAUCUACAUCAGCUGACCAUAACUAUGCUGUGGAUAAGGGGUGGUGGGAUCAGAACUGAUAACCAUUUUCAACAAAUUUCAUACGAAUGUGUCUUAGAAGCCUCAUUUAGAUGCGAUGUCAUUCAUGGGUAAAAUUGAAAUGUGCCUUCACUGGCAGAGUCUUUAACAAUCUCUGCAAGACAAUCUACGCUUUUUUCUAUUGUUUCUGAAAAUCCUUUCAACCUCUAUUCAAAGCCAUUUUCUCACUUUAGAAAUUGAUUACAGCAGGGCUGUGAUUGUCAGUACAAAAAUCUGUACAGGGAUAUGGCAGUGGUAUAAUAGAUGACCAUUUCCAAUUAUAAAACAAUUAGCAAAGUAUAGCUAGGUCAGGCCACUAGUACCCUUCAAAUUCUUAACCAUAUUUACAAAGACAGCUUUUCAUAACUUUUAUUGCUCUGUCCACAAAGAUGUGGUCUCAUGGUUUCACACGAUUGAGAAUGCUACAAGUAAUAGUAUACUGAAAAGAACAUGUCUCUAAUUCUGGACUGCUCUUUAUCUCCAAGAAACAGAGAGAGAGAGAAUGAAAAAAAAUCCCAGCUUAGAGGAAUUUUGGAAGUUACUCUUUCAUGAACCAUCACAUUUUCUGGGCCUUUGUAAUCUUUAAACACUGUUACUCUUUAGAGGUUGGUUUGAAUUUGUUGCACAGAGAACAAUAAUCUAUGACAAAUUAAUGAACCCUUUUGCUAAUAUCACAUGAGUACAAGUAUCUUGUAUUUCUCAUCACAUUUACCGUAAUAAAGAAUGCAGACAAGUAUAAUACAUGGCAUCAUUUUGGGGAUUUUCCAAUUUCUAUGUGGGCAUACUGGAAGAAGUUUGUAACAGUUGCAAUUCUGUCACAAUGCAGGAAGUCUUUCUAGAACACACAAUGUGGAUGAUUUUCAGUUUUAGAAUUGUAAACUAACCAAAUGUCAAUUCAGUUUCUCAUUUUAUAUUAGUUUUUGUUACAAACACUGCCUAUUUCUCUUUUGUACAAACACUUCACACACACACACACACACACGCGCACACACACACACACACACACACACACACAGGCACACACACACUAGAUGGGCCUCCAAAAGAACUCAGAGCUGCUGUCUUCCUCUGGGAGGUUGAUCAUAUGUCUAUUCAGUUGGGAGAAUGGAGCAGUCAAGUUCAAAAUCCAUGUGGCUCUCUGGCUUCAGAAGCUAUCCUUUCAGCUAUGACACACACACUAAAUAGUAUUGCCCAGGUUUGCCCUACAACAUGUUAGCAUAUCUACAUAUUUUGUACUGUAAUAAUGUGUACGCUCUUAAUAAUUUGUUUUUAAUGCUGUGUAAAGUUAGCAAUUAGAGUAAGAGAAACGUAUGGGAUAAUGAUUGAGUAAAAUCUCAGCUCCUUUUGAGUCAAUCACUCAGCUUGUUGGCACAGUAGAUAUUUAUGACCUUAAAUACUGUCAGCGCUUCACAGCACAUUACUGAGGCCUGGAUAAAGCAUUCACACAAAGAUAAAUGGAUUGAAACUGUGUCAAUUUUGUAGAAAAAGAUAUUCUGGGGUUUAGUAACAGAGAAUUUUUCUUUCCUUACUGCGAUUAAUAAAGUGGAACUCCAAUUGCAAGUAACUAUUCAGUUUUAUGUUCUUCACAUAUGGAAACCUCUCUGUCACUAAUACCCUGGGACAAACUGGAUGAUUACCAUCCAAGUGUUAUUUUCUUCCUCGAAAAUUUCAAAACCAGAAUGAAUUAGUUCUCCAAGUCUGGCUAUACUAUAGUUUUCUUCUUAAUGUAAAACAGCUGAAUAAAACAGCUUGAACAAUAUUUGACUUUCAUGGGUCUUAAGAACGUUUCAAAAUACACCACCAAUAUAUUUACCAACAUAUUUAGUGCCAGAUAUACACAGAACAAACACUACCCUAUUGUUUCUGUGUGCGUGUGUGUGUGUCUGUGUCUGUGUGUGUGUGUAGCAGGACACUAAAUAAACAAGUCAUGUUGCUGUUCUUAGGGAAGUUUUGGUAAAGAGAGCUUCAAAGUUCCUUGGAGUCACCUGCAAGGCUAACUGUACUAAAAGCGGAAUUUGCAUGAUCUUUCUACAAACUCUCAGUGUAAAGUGGUAGAUAGACAUGCAAGCAUCACACUUAGAUUGCAAUAAAUGCUGUGAUGUAAAAAAUACAAUGGAGGAAAAAUUUUUGAUUAGGGAAAUUUAAACAUUUUCAAAGAAGAGUUAAUGUUUCAGUGGAGUCUUAAAAGAUGAGUAGGAAUUCAACAGCCAGAAGGGAAGUGUAGACGCUCUGUGUCACAUAAAACAAAACAGAACAGAAUAGUAUAAGUGAAGGCAUAGAGCUUCACAUGAAAGGCACAUGAAAUAGCACUGGGUAUCUCUAAAAUAUUAAUUAGCCUAGUGUAGCUGGACAAUGAGGGGCAGAGCCCCUGGUAUGCAAGUGAUGUCUGGGAAAGGAGCAAUCUUUCUACAGUGCCUCAUUCCAUCAUACCUCAUUACCAGAAAAACAUUAUGAGCCACUUAGGCCUGUAUUAUUUGAGCAUCUCUGAAAUGGAGUUGCUCUACAUGUUUUGUAGAAACCUAAUGAGUAAUUUAUUCUCAUCAGUAGACAAAAUGAAAGAAAGAAAAUAGACUCUGAGCAAAGUAUGAUUCACAACCUUGCCUAUUAGGCUAUAGAAGAUUGCCCUACUAAUUCCUCCUUUUCGUCUGUUGAACAAUCUGUAUUUUGCCUGCUCAAAAAGGAAUUCCUCAAGUUAUAGGGGCAGUUUGACCAGUACAAUCAUAUCAGAAAAAAAUCAGCAAAAUUAUGUUCUAACAACAUCUUCCCAUCUAAAGUGCACAUUUUAUUUUUUUAAGGUAACAUAAUUACUACGAACAACCGAAAUGGUAUAUAAAGGUGAAAAAUUAAAAUAAUUUUUUUUACAGCUCCACGUUACCUCACCCCCUAGACCCUGGUAACCACCAUUCAACUCUCUGUUUCCAUUAGUUCAACUUUUUAAGAUUCUUUUUAUACAAAGGAUGUCAUGUAGCAUUUUUUUCUUUUUUCAUCUGGCUUAUUUCACUUAGUUUGCUUAUUUCAACGUGCUCUGAAGUUUCAUCCAUGUUUAUGUAAAUGGAAGGAGCUCCCUCUUUAUAUGGCUAAGAUAUAUAUAUAUAUUAUAUUAUAUAUAUAUAUGUAUAUAUAUAUAUUAUAUAUAUAUAUGUAUAUAUAUAUAAUUUUCUUUCUUCAUUCAUCUGUCCGUGGGCACUUAGGUUGUUCCAUAACUUAUCUAUUGUGAAUAAUGGUGCAAUGGGAAUGAAUGGGAGUGCAGAUGUCUGUUUGGCAUACUGAUUUAAUUUCCUUUGGAUAUAUAACCAGAAGUGGGAAUGCUGGAUCAUACAGUAGUUCUAUUUUUACUUUUAUGAGGAUCUCCAUACUGUUUUACAUAAUGGCUUACUAAUUUACAUUCCCAUAAACAGUGUACAAGAAUACCUCCUUGCCAACACAUUAUCUUUUAAGUUUUGGAUAAUAUUAUUCCUAUUAAUAACAUGUGUGAUAUUACAUUGUGGUUUUGAUUUGCAUUUCCCUUAUGAUUAAUGAUGUUAAGUACCUUUUCAGAUAUAUGUUGGCCAUUUGUAUGUCUUCCUUGGAGAGAUGUCUAUUCAGCUCCUUGGUCCAUUUUUCAAAAUACAGUUUACUUGUAUUUUUGCUAUUGACUUGUAUGAGUUCCUUAUAUAUUUUGGAUAUUAACCCCUUAUGAGAAAUAUGGUUUGCAAAUAUUUUCUCCUAUUCUGCAGGUUGCCUUUUCGUUUUGUCGAUUAUUUCCUUUGCUGGGCAGAUAAUUUUUUUAUUUUAUUUUUUGAAACAGUGUCUCACUCUGUCACCCAGGCUGGAGUGCAGUGGUGUGAUCAUGUCUCACCACAGCCUUGACCUCCCCAGGAUCAGGUGAUCCUCCCACCUCAGUUUUUGUAUUUUUAGUAGAGAUGGAGUUUCACCCUGUUGCCCAGGCUGGUCUAAAACUCCUGGGCUCAAGCCAUCUUGCCCACCUUGGGACCUCCCAAAGUGUUAGGAUUAGAGGCAUGGGCCACCAUGCCUGGCUUUGAAACUUUUUAAUUUAAUGUAGUCUGACUUGUUUAUUUUUACUUUGUUGCAUGUGCUUUUGGUGUUACAGCCAAAAAAGUUAUUGCCAAGACCAAUGCCAUAGACAUUAUUUCUUAUUCUAGUAAUUUUACAAUUUUAGGUCUUAUGUUUAAGUUUUUAAUCGAUUUUGAGUUGAUUUUUGUGUAUGGUAUAGGAUAAAGGUCCAAUUUCAUUAUUUUGUAUUUGGAUAUUCAAUGUUUAAAAUACGAUUUAUUGAAUGGACUAUAUUUCCCCAUGAUGUGUUUUUAGUGCCUUUGUUGAAGAUUUGUUGAUCAUAUAUGUGUGGAUUUGUUUCUUGGCUUUCUAUUCUGUUCCAUUGGUCUAUGUGUCUGCUUCUAUGCCAAUACCAUACUGUUUUGAUUACUAUAGCUUUACAAUAUAAUUUGAAAUCAGGAAAUGUUCUAAACUUCUUUCUCAAGAUUGUUUUAGAUCUUUGGGGACUUAGGUGGUUCCAUAAGGUUUUAAGAAUUUUUUUUCUAUUUCUGUAAAAAAUUAUAUUAAGAUUUUGAUAGUGCUUGCAUUGACUCUGUAGAUCACUUUGGUUAGUAUCAACAUUUUUGCAAAAUUAAUUCUUCCAAACUAUGAACACAGGAUACUGUUGCACUUAUUUCUCUUCUUCAAUUCCUUUCAUCAGUAUCUUAUAGUUUUUAAUGUACAGAUUUUUCACCUCCUUGGUUAAACUUAUUCCUAAGUACAUUUUCCUUUUUGAUGCAAUUGCAAAUGGGAUUGUUUUUCUAAUUUAUUUUAUUUUGUUUGUUUGUUUGUUUGUUUGUUUUUGAGAUGGAGUCUUGCUCUGUCACCCAGGCUGGAGUGCAGUGGUGUGAUCUUGGCUCACCACAACCUCUGCCUCCCGAGUUAAAGGGAUUCUCUUGCCUCAGCCUCCCGAGUAGCUGGGAUUAUAGGCGCCUACCACCAUGCCUGGCUAAUUUUUGUAUUUUUAGUAGAUAGAGAUGGGGUUUCACCAUGUUGGCCAGGCUAGUCUCAAACUCCUGACCUCAGGUGAUCCACCUUCCUCGGCCUCCCAAAGCGCUGGGAUUACAGGCGUGAGCCACUGCACCCAGCCACUAAUUUAUUUUUUGGAUAGUUCAUUGUUAGUGUACAGAAACAACUGAUUUUUUAUGUUGAUUUUGUAUCAACAUUGGUGAAUUCCACCCAACAUUUGAGGAAAAACUAAUACCAAUCCUUCUCAAAAUCUUCCAAAAAAAUGAAGAGGAAGGAGCACUUCCAAACUCAUUUUAUGAAGCCAGCAUUAUUCUCAUACCAUUCCAGACAAGGACACUACAAGAAAAAAAAUUACAGGCCCAAAUCCCUGUUGAACAUAGAUGCAAAAAUCCACAACAAAAUACUAGCUAAAAGAACUUAACAUCACAUUUAAAGGAUCAUUCACCAUAAUCAAGUGGGAUUUCACCAAUUUCACUUGGGUAGAAUUCACCAAUGUUGAUAAAAAAAUCAACAUAAAAAUCAGUUGUUUCUUCACACGAACAAUGAACUAUCCAAAAAAUAAAGAACACAAUCCCAUUUGCAAUUGCAAAAAAAUACUUAGAAAUAAAUUUAGCAAAGGAGGUGAAAGAUCUUUAUAUUAAAAACUAUAAAAUAUUGAUGAAAGUAAUUGAAGAAGACAAAUGGAACAGAUCCCUUUGUUCAUAGAUUGGAAGAAUUAAUAUUACAGAAAUGUUAAUACUAACUAAAGUGAUCUACAGAGUCAAUGCAAGCCCUAUCAAAAUCUUAAUCGAAUCUUUUACAGAAAUAAAAAAAAAUUCUAAAAUUCAUAUGGCACCACAUAAGUCCCCAAAAAUCUUUACAACUUCACUGAAUUUAUUUAUCACUUCUAACAUUUUUCUGUUGGAGUCAUUGGGUUUCUGUAUUGAAGAGCAUGUGAUUUGAAACAGACCAUUUUACUUCUUCCGUCCUGAUUUGCAUGCAUUUUAUUUCUUUUUCUCGACUUAUUGCUCUAAGCAGAACUUCAAGUACCAUGUGGAAUAGAAGUGGCAAGAGUGAGCAUUCUCUUCUUCAUCCUGAUUUCAGAAGAAAAGCUUUCAGCAUUUCACUACUGACUAUCACGUUAGAUGUGAGUUUGUCAUAUAUAUGGCCUUUGUUAUAUUUAGGGAUAUUCCUUCUCUACCUAAUGUUUUGAAUGUUUUCAUCAUGAAAGGGUGUUGAUUUUUUUUCAAAUGCCUUUUCUGUAUCUGUUAAAAUGAUCAUAUGAUUAUUAUCCUUCAUUGUCUUAUUGUUCAUAUUUAUUGAUUUGAGUAUGUUGAGCCAUCCUUUUAUCCCAGGGAUAACUCUCACUUGAUUAUGGUGAAUGAUCUUUUUAAUGUGAUGUUAAGUUCUUUUAGCUAGUAUUUUGUUGUGGAUUUUUGCAUCUAUGUUCAACAGGGAUUUGGGACUGUAUUCCUUUUUUUUCUUGUAGUGUCCUUGCCUGGCUUUGGUAGGAGAAUAAUGCUGGUUUCAUAGAAAAAUGAGUUUAGAAGUGUUCCUCACUCUUCUUUUUUUUUUGGAAGAUUUGAGAAGGAUUGAUAUUAGAUUUUCUUUAAAUGUUGGGUAGAAUUCACCACUGAAGCCAUCUGGUUCUGGGCUUUACUUUGUUGGGAAGUUCUUUUUUAAAAAAUUGCUGAUUCAAUAUUCUUUUUCAUUAUUGCUCUCUACAGAUUCUCUAUUCAUGAUUCAGUCUUGCUAGGUUGUGGUAUGUUUCUAGAAAUUUAUCUGUUUCUUCUAGAUUACCCAACUUGUGUAUAAUUGUUCAUAAUAGUCUCUAAUGAUCAUUUAUAUUUCUAUGGUAUCAGUUGUAAUGUCUUCUCUUUCAUUUCUGAUUUUAUUUGUUUAUGUCUUUUCUCUUUCACUCUCAGUUACUCUAGCUAAAGGCUUGUCUGUUUUUUAAUCUUUUCAAAAAACAACUCAGUUUUAUUGCUCUUUUUUAUUUUUCUAGUUUCUAUUUCACUUUUUUCUGUUCUGAUAUUUACUUCAUUCCUUCUUCCGACUUUGGGAUUAGUUUAUGGUUCUUUUAUAGUUCCUUGAGGUGUAAAGUUAGGUCGUUUAUUUGAUUUUUUUUUUCUUAAUGUAGGCAUUUAUCACUAUAAACUUCCUUCUUAGAAAUGCCUUUUGCUGCAUCCCAUAUAUUUUGGUAUGUUGUUUUUCCACUUUUGUUUGUCUCAAGUUUUUUAAAUUUUUCUUUUGAUUUGCUCUUUGAUUCUUUGGCUAUUUAGGAGUGUAUUGUUUAAUUUUACAGUUUUCCUCCCUUUACUGAUUUCCAGUUUCUUAGCAUUGUGGUCAGAAAAGAUAUUUGGUAUGAUUUCAAUCUUCUUAGUUUUGUUAACACUUGUUUUGUGGCCUAACAGUUGAUGUAUCUUCAAAAUGUACCUGCGCAAUUACUUGGGACGAAUGUACAUUCUAUUGCUUUUGGAGGGAAUGUUUUGUAUCUGUUAGGUCCAUUUGGUCUAAAGUGUAGUUCAAGUCAAUUCCCUAUUGAUUUUCUGUCUGGGUGAUCUGUCCAUUGUUGAAAGCUGGGUAUCAAAGUCUUCUACUACUAUACUAUUACAGUCUAUAUUUCCUGUUCAUAUCUAUUAAUACCUGCUUUAUAUAUUUAGGUGAUCCAAUGUUGGGUGUGUAUAUAUUCAAAAUUGCAUCUUGUUGAUGAAUUGACUCAUUUAUUUUUAUAUAAUGGCAUUCUUUGUCUCUUGUUACAGUUUGUGACUUUAAGUCUGUUUUGUCUGAUAUAGUAUAGGUGUCUCUGCUUCUUUCUGGUUUCUAUUUACAUGCAAUAUCUUUUUAAUCUCUUCACUUUCAGUUUAUACGUGUCCUUGCAGCUAAAGUGACUAUCUUAUAGAUAGCAAGUACUUAGUUCUUCCUUUUUCAUCCAUUCAGCCACUCACUGUCUUUUGAUUAGAGAAUUUAAUCUACUUACAUUAAAAUUAAUUAUUUAUAGGUAAAGACAUACUAUUGCUACUUUGUUAAAUGUUUUUCAGCUGUUUUGUAAGUUUUUUUGUUUCUUUCUUCCUCUCUUGCUGUCUUUCUUUGUGAUUGAUGAUUUUCCUGUAGUACUAUGGUUUGAUUUCUUUUUUUUUAAUAAUUUUUAUUUUUAUUUUAAGUUCCAGGGUACAUGUGCAGGAUAUGCAGGUUUGUUACAUAGGUAAACAUGUGCCAUGGUGGUUUGCUGCACCUUCAACCCAUCACUGAGGUGUUCAGCCAAGCAUGCAUUAGCUAUUUUUCCUAAUAGUAUCUCUCCCCACACCCCACCCCCCUUGACAGGCCCCAGUGUGUAUUGUUCCCCUCCCUGUGUCCAUGUGUUCUCAUGUUCAGCUCUCACUUAUAAGUGAGAAUACGCAGUGUUUGGUUUUCUGUUCCUGCAAUAGCUUGCUAAGAAUAAUGGCUUCCAGCGCCAUGUGUGUCCCUGAAAAUGACAUGAUCUCAUUCCUUUUUAUGGCUGCAUAGUAUCCCAUGGUGUAUAUGUGCCACAUUUUCUUUAUCCACUGUAUCAUUGAUGGGCAUUUGGGUUGAUUCCACAUCUUUGCUCUUUUGAACAGUGCUGCAGUGAACAUAUGCGUGCAUGUAUCUUUGUAAUAGAAUGAUUUAUAUUCCUUUGGGUAUAUACCUAGUAAUGGGAUUGCUGGGUCAAAUGUUAUUUCUGGUUCUAGAUCUCGGAGAAAUCACCACACUGUCUUCCACAAUGUUUGAACUAAUUUACUUUCCCACCAGCAGUGUAAAAGUGUUCCUAUUUCUCUGCAACCUUGCCAGCAUCUGUCAUUUUUUGACUUUUUAAUAAUCACCAUUGUGACUGGCAUGAGAUGGUAUCUCCUUGUGGUUCUGAUUUGCAUUUCUUUAAUGAUCAGUGAUGUUGAACUUUUUUCAUAUGUUCGUUGGCCUCAUGAAUGUCUUUUUUUGAGAAGUGUCUGUUCAUGUCCUUUGCCCACUUUUUGAUGCGGUUUUUUUUUUCUUGUAUAUUUGCUUAAAUUCCUUGUAGAUUCUGGAUAUUAGACCGUUGUCAGAUGGAUAGAUUGCAAAAAUUUUCUCCCACUCUGUAGGUUGCAUGUUCACUGUGAUAGUUUCUGUCUUUCUUUCUUUUUAUAUUAUACUUGAAGUUCUGGGGUACAUGUGCAGAAUGUGCAGGUUUGUUACAUAGGUAUGCACGUGCCAUGGUGGUUUGCUGCACCCAUCAACCCGUCAUCUAUAUUAAGUGUUUCUCCUAAUGCUUUGACUUCAUUAUUUCUUUCAUUUGAUUGAGUAUGCUGUGGAUGUUUUCUGUUACUUUUUUAAUUUUAUUCAUUGUAUUCUUCAGCUUCAGAAUUUGUUUGUUUGUUUGUUUGUUUGUUUUUCACAGUUUCUAUCUCUUUGUUGAACUUAUUAUUUUGGUCAUACAUUGUUUUCCUGAUUCUACUGACUUCUUUGUCUGUGUUCUCAUGUAGCAACCCAAGCUUAUUUAAAACAAUUAUUUUUAAUAUUUUGUCAGGAAAUUUGUAGAUCUCCAUUUUUUUUUGUUGGCAACUGGAAAAUUACUGAGUUUCUUCGGUGGUAUUAUUUUUGUGUUGUUUUUGGCAGGUGUUCCUUGAAAUCUCGUGUUGCCAUGUUCACAUUUGAAGAAGUAGUCUCCUCCUUCAGCCUAUACUGACUGGCUUCAGAAGAGAAACAGUUAUACCAGUUAGCCUGACUGGGGAUACUAAGACUCUUGCACAUCUUUUCUGUAGAUGUGUCACUCAAGCUCUUUUUGAGAAAUUUUAAGAUCAUCUGUAUUUUCUUAAUUUCAUAAAACCAAACCAAAUUCUGAGAGUUUCCCAUUUGUUUUCUCUAACGUGGUGCCCUGAAGUGCUCAAGUUUUUGUGCCUUCUCCCAUUCCCACAGAGUCAAGCUGCCUGCUUCUGCAUGCACACAAGUUCACACUCGCUGUCAGGGUUUGGGCCGUGUGCAGGGAGCAAGCCAAGGUAGAGGAGAGAGGGAGACAUGCAAAGUUUUGGGAGCACCCAUGUGUCAGCUUCGGGGGUUUACAGUUCAGGCAUCCCAAGCCACUAGUGGGUGGGCCUCCUGAUGGAGUCUGUGAAGUUGUUAGUAGUAUAUGUGUCCUUUUGUUGAAUUUCCAGUCUCUGGUUGCUGUGAGCCCCUACCGCUGUUCCCUGCUCACAGCCUCUCAGUCACUCAGACAUGAUGAUCCCCUCAGUAUUCUGAGUGGGGAUAGAAAGAAGUAGGCCUCUUGGUCAGUGUCCCACGUGGCUAGGAAAGCCAGGCAUUCAUUUACUACACUCUCCCUUUCACCCAAUGGAGAAAUCAUGAGUCAAAGUUGUAUCUCUUGGUGUUGAGUUCUGCUAGCUUGAGAGACGGUUGACAUAAGUAGUGAAACUAUUUUCUGGUUCUUUUCAAUGUGCCUAUUCUCGUAAUUGUUUUGCUCCAUCUGUGAGCUGGACUACCAGACUCCCACAAAGGUACUCUCAUACUUGAGUGGUUGUCAAAAUUGUAGAUAGUGGGGAAAUGACAGGAGAAAAUUCCUGUUCUGCCAUCUUGCUGACAUCACCCCAAUAUCUAAAAUGCAUAUUUUAAUUAUUUUUUUCCUUGAAUAAAGUUUAUUUUGGAAUUGUUGAGUUUUACAAAAUAAUUUAAAAUAUUCUCUCUCUCUCUCUCUCUCUCUGGGGUUGAGGUCUCACUCUGUCACCCAGGAUGGAUUACAGUGGCACAAUCGCAGCUCACUGCAGCCUCGAAUUUCUUGGGUCAAGUGAUCCUCCCACUUCAGCCUCCCAAGUAGCUGGGACUACAAGGCGUGUGCCACCAUGCCCAGCUAAUAUUUUUACAUUUUUUGUAGAGAUGGGGUCUCACUAUGUUGCCCAGGUGGGUCUUGAACUCCUGGCAUCAUGUGGUCCUCCCACCUCCACCUCCCAAGUCCUGAGGAUACCAAUUGUGAGUCACUGUGCCCAGCUAUCCCCUUCUCACUCUCUUUUUCUCUCACACACAUGUGUGCAUGCACAGACACACACACCUCAUGUUCAUUCUCUUUACCAUGAUGAUCCUUGGUUCUUUUACACAGCUUCUUUCAGUUUACCUUACAAUUUAGCUCAACACAAAUUUUAAAAAACUUAUAGUUACAAUUUAAUUUGGCUUGGUCCACACCUCUAACAAAUUUGAUACAAUCUCCAACUUACGGUUGCAAGUUAGUUGAUUAUAUUCACUUCCAAGUAUUUCCCCCAACAUUUCAUUAUGAAAAUAUAUCCAUCAAUUAAUGCUCUUAUCUAUAAAAUAAUUAUUUUUUUGCAUUUCAAAAUAAGUUACAGACAUCAAUGCACUUCAUCUUUAAACCCUUUAUCAUGCAUAUCAGGAAGUAGAGUUUAAUAUUUCUAUAUUUCUUGGGGGAGAAAUGGAGCUAAAAUUAUAUACUGUAUCAUAUACAAACCUGUUAGGUAUAUCAAUUCAUGUGUAUUGACAAAUGCGUGCACCAUGUAACAGAAACUCCUUUCAAGAUAUAGAAUAUUCCUAUCACUACAAAUAUUAAUCACCAAAACAAUGGGGAGAAUGUCUCUAGGGCAUGUCAGAGACCUUCACUGCAGCCUCUCCCAUUAUAGGCCAGGAGGCCUUGAAGGAAAAAAAUGGUUUAGUGGGCCAGGCCUCAGGCACCCCCCCUUGCUCUUUGCAGCCUUGAAACAUGGUACCCUGCGUCCCCAGCUGCUUCAGCUUCAGCUGUGGCUAAAAGGGGCCAACAUACAGCUCAGGCCAUUGUUUCAGAGAGUGCAAUCCCCAAGCUUUGGCAGCUUACACAUGGUGUUGGGCUUGCAGGAGCACAGAAGUCAAGAAUUGAGGUUUGGGAACCUCUGCCUAGAUUUCAGAGGAUGUAUGGAAAUGCCUGGAUGUCCAGACAGAAGUCUGCUGCAGGGGUAGAGCUCUCAGGGAGAACCUCUGCUAGGGCAGUGCAGAAGGGAAAUGUGGGGUUGGAGCUCCCCCACAGAGUCUUCACUGGGGCACUGUAUAGUGGAGCUCUGAGAAGAGGGCCAUAGUCCUCCAGACCCCAGAAUGGUAGAUCCACCAAUAGCUUGCACCAUGCACCUGGAAAAGCCACUGGCACUCAACACCAGCCCAUGAAAAGAGCUGUGAGGGUGGCUGCAUCCUGCAAAGCCACAGGGGAAGAGCUGCCCAAGGCUGUGGGAGCCCACCCCUUGCAUCAUUGUGACCUGGAUAGAUGUGAGACAUGGAGCCUAAGGAGAUCAUUUUGGAACUUUAAGCUUUAACGACUGCCCUAUUGGAUUUUGGACUUGCAUGGGCCUAUAGCCCCUUUGUUUUGGCCAACUUCUCCCAUUUGGAAUGGGUAUUUUUACUCAAUUCCUGUACCCCCAUUGUAUCUUGGAAAUAACUAACUUGCUUUAGAUUUUACAGGCUUAUAGGUGGAAGGGACUUGCUUUGUCUCAGAUGAGACUUUGGACUUGGACUUCUGGGUUAAUGUUUGAAUGAGUUAAUACUUUGGGGGACUAUUGGAAGGGCAUGAUUGUGUUUUGAAAUGUGAGAACAUGAGAUUUGGGAGGAACUAGGGUCAGAAUGAUAUGGUUUGGUUUUGUGUUCCCACCCAAAUCUCUCCUUGAAUUGUAAUAAUCCCCAUGUGUCAGGGGUGGGACCAGGUGGAGGACUGAAUCAUGGGGGUGGUUUCCCUCAUGCUAUUCUCAUGAUAGUGAUUUAUAACAGAUCCAAUGGUUUUAUAAGCAUCUGGCAUUUCCCCUGCUGGCACUCAUUCUCUCUCCUGCCACCCUGUGAAGAGGGGCCUUCCACCAUGAUUGUAAGUCUCCUGAGGCCUCCGAAGCCAUGCGGAACUGUGAGUCAGUUAAAACUCUUUCCUUUAUAAAUUACCUAGUCUUGGGUAUUUCUUUAUGGAAGCAUGAGAAUGAACUAAUGCACAGGGUAAAAAUUUAAAAACAAACAUACAAAUGCAAGUAAACAAGCCAAUAUUUCAACUGUUCCCAUUGCAUUAUCCUUAUUCUUUAUCUAUGGUACCAGAAAAUAAUACAUCUGAAACAAUUUUUUUUUCCUGCCAUGAUGUACACUCAAGUGGGUCCACUGGGGUUUCUUUCAGUUUCCCAAAUACUAGAUAUGACUCUUCCCUAUACCUUAUCUUCAUAUGAAGAAAGCUAUGAGAAUAUAUUAAUAACUGAAUAUAGUAACACUACUAUAGGAAUAAGCAUGUGUAUAUUCCAACUGAUCUUUUAAAACUUUUAUUUUGAAAUAUUUAUAGAUUCAAAGGAAGAUGCAAAGAGUAUAGGGAAGUGCUAUAUGCCCUUUAUCUAGUUCCUCUAGUGGUAUCAACUUACAUAACUGCAGUAUCAUAUAUAAACCAAGAAAUUGGCAUCUGUAUAAUCCACAGACAUUACUCAGACUUCUCUAGUUUUACAUACACUAAUUUGUAUGUGUGUGUGUGUGUGCGUGCACGUUUAUGUGUGUAGGUCUAUGCAAUUUUACCACAUGUGUAUAUUUGGGUAACCACUACAAUGAUCAAGAUAUGGAACUGUUCCGUCACCACUAAGAUCCCUUGUGCUAUUCCUUUAUAAACAUCUCCCUGUCAUCCUUUUUCACCCAUAAAAGCUAGUAAACACUAAUCUGUUCUUCAUCCUUAUAAUUUUAUUAUUUCAGAAUUGUUAUAUAAAUGUCAUCAUACAGUAUAUAACACAUAGAGAUUGGCUUUUGUCACUCAGCACAAUUCCCUUGAGAUGCAUCCAAACUGUUGUGUAUAUCAGUAAUGCAAUAUGUUUAAUUUCUGUGUAGUAUUCCAUGGUAGAGAUGUGCCAUAGUUUAACUAUUCACCUGUUGAACAACAUUUGUGUUCUUUCUACUUUUGGGCUAUUACAAAUAAAGUUGCUAUGAACAUUCAUGUAUAA